AUCACACCUUCCUCCUGCCCUGACUUCUCAUAUCUUGCCUAGGAACUCCAGGCUUGUCUUGGCUCCAAAUGGAUCCCAACUGCUCCUGCACCACAGGUGGCUCCUGUGCCUGCGCCGGCUCCUGCAAGUGCAAAGAGUGCAAAUGUACCUCCUGCAAGAAGUGCUGCUGCUCUUGCUGCCCCGUGGGCUGUGCCAAGUGUGCCCAGGGCUGUGUCUGCAAAGGCUCAUCAGAGAAGUGCCGCUGCUGUGCCUGAUGUUGGGAGAGCCCUGCUCCCAGACAUAAAUAGAGCAACCAGUACUAACCUGGAUUUUUUUUUUUAACUACCCUGACCGGUUUGCUACAUUCUUUUUUCUAUUCAAUAUGUGAAAGACAAUAAAACACUUUUGACUUGA